CCUUUCUCGAGGCUGUGGCCUCCGCGAGAGCCGAGCGGGCCGCACCGCCGGCCGUGCGACUGCCCCAGUCAGACACGACCCCGGCUUCUAGCCCGCCUAAGCCUGUUUGGGGUUGCUGACUCGUUUCCUCCCCGAGUUUCCCGCGGGAACUAACUCUUCAAGAGGACCAACCGCAGCCCAGAGCUUCGCAGACCCGGCCAACCAGAGGCGAGGUUGAGAGCCCGGCGGGCCGCGGGGAGAGAGCGUCCCAUCUGUCCUGGAAAGCCUGGGCGGGUGGAUUGGGACCCCGAGAGAAGCAGGGGAGCUCGGCGGGGUGCAGAAGUGCCCAGGCCCCUCCCCGCUGGGGUUGGGAGCUUGGGCAGGCCAGCUUCACCCUUCCUAAGUCCGCUUCUGGUCUCCGGGCCCAGCCUCGGCCACCAUGUCCCGCCAGACCACCUCUGUGGGCUCCAGCUGCCUGGACCUGUGGAGGGAAAAGAAUGACCGGCUCGUUCGACAGGCCAAGGUGGCUCAGAACUCCGGUCUGACUCUGAGGCGACAGCAGUUGGCUCAGGAUGCACUGGAAGGGCUCAGAGGGCUCCUCCAUAGUCUGCAAGGGCUCCCUGCAGCUGUUCCUGUUCUUCCCUUGGAGCUGACUGUCACCUGCAACUUCAUUAUCCUGAGGGCAAGCUUGGCCCAGGGUUUCACAGAGGAUCAGGCCCAGGAUAUCCAGCGGAGCCUAGAGAGAGUGCUGGAGACACAGGAGCAGCAGGGGCCCAGGUUGGAACAGGGGCUCAGGGAGCUGUGGGACUCUGUCCUUCGUGCUUCCUGCCUUCUGCCGGAGCUGCUGUCUGCCCUGCACCGCCUGGUUGGCCUGCAGGCUGCCCUCUGGUUGAGUGCUGACCGUCUUGGGGACCUGGCCUUGUUACUAGAGACCCUGAAUGGCAGCCAGAGUGGAGCCUCUAAGGAUCUGCUGUUACUUCUGAAAACUUGGAGUCCCCCAGCUGAGGAAUUAGAUGCUCCAUUGACCCUGCAGGAUGCCCAGGGAUUGAAGGAUGUCCUCCUGACAGCAUUUGCCUACCGCCAAGGUCUCCAGGAGCUGAUCACAGGGAACCCAGACAAGGCACUAAGCAGCCUUCAUGAAGCGGCCUCAGGCCUGUGUCCACGGCCUGUGUUGGUCCAGGUGUACACAGCACUGGGGUCCUGUCACCGUAAGAUGGGAAAUCCACAGAGAGCACUGUUGUACUUGGUUGCAGCCCUGAAAGAGGGAUCAGCCUGGGGUCCUCCACUUCUGGAGGCCUCUAGGCUCUAUCAGCAACUGGGGGACACAACAGCAGAGCUGGAGAGUCUGGAGCUGCUAGUUGAGGCCUUGAAUGUCCCAUGCAGUUCCAAAGCCCCGCAGUUUCUCAUUGAGGUAGAAUUACUACUGCCACCACCUGACCUAGCCUCACCCCUUCAUUGUGGCACUCAGAGCCAGACCAAGCACAUACUAGCAAGCAGGUGCCUACAGACGGGGAGGGCAGGAGACGCUGCAGAGCAUUACUUGGACCUGCUGGCCCUGUUGCUGGAUAGCUCGGAGCCAAGGUUCUCCCCACCCCCCUCCCCUCCAGGGCCCUGUAUGCCUGAGGUGUUUUUGGAGGCAGCGGUAGCACUGAUCCAGGCAGGCAGAGCCCAAGAUGCCUUGACUCUAUGUGAGGAGUUGCUCAGCCGCACAUCAUCUCUGCUACCCAAGAUGUCCCGGCUGUGGGAAGAUGCCAGAAAAGGAACCAAGGAACUGCCAUACUGCCCACUCUGGGUCUCUGCCACCCACCUGCUUCAGGGCCAGGCCUGGGUUCAACUGGGUGCCCAAAAAGUGGCAAUUAGUGAAUUUAGCAGGUGCCUCGAGCUGCUCUUCCGGGCCACACCUGAGGAAAAAGAACAAGGGGCAGCUUUCAACUGUGAGCAGGGAUGUAAGUCAGAUGCGGCACUGCAGCAGCUUCGGGCAGCCGCCCUAAUUAGUCGUGGACUGGAAUGGGUAGCCAGCGGCCAGGAUACCAAAGCCUUACAGGACUUCCUCCUCAGUGUGCAGAUGUGCCCAGGUAAUCGAGACACUUACUUUCACCUGCUUCAGACUCUGAAGAGGCUAGAUCGGAGGGAUGAGGCCACUGCACUCUGGUGGAGGCUGGAGGCCCAAACUAAGGGGUCACAUGAAGAUGCUCUGUGGUCUCUCCCCCUGUACCUAGAAAGCUAUUUGAGCUGGAUCCGUCCCUCUGAUCGUGACGCCUUCCUUGAAGAAUUUCGGACAUCUCUGCCAAAGUCUUGUGACCUGUAGCUGCCACGUUUUGAAGAGCUUGAGCUGGGUCCCCAGUGGGCUGUCUCUCUGUGGGGAGGGCUUUCUGCUUCACCAUCAUUAGGAAUGUGACCAUUCCUAUAUAAUUCCUGGACUGGUGAGAUUGGUGGUAGGCCUGUGAAAUUUGCCCUAGUUACUACCAUUCUCGUUUUGGAGGAAACAAUCUCUGCCACCACCAAGUCAUUGACUUUGCUCGAGGCACCUUUUUUCCUGUUUCUCCUUUUCUGUUGUCGAGUAAAAUUUCAUAUUUA